AGCGAAAGGGACUUCCGGGAGAUCUAGGAAGUCGCUUCUUUUUCUGGUAGAAGGCGGGGUUCUCCUCGUACGCUGCGGAGUCUCUGCGGGGUGUAGACCGGAAUCCUGCUGACGGGCAGAGUGGAUCAGGGAGGGAGGGUCGAGACACGGUGGCUGCAGGUCUGAGACAAGGCUGCUCCGAGGUAGUAGCUCUCUUGCCUGGAGGUGGCCAUUCAUUCCUGGAGUGCUGCUGAGGAGCGAGGGCCCAUCUGGGGUCUCUGGAAGUCGGUGCCCAGGCCUGAAGGAUAGCCCCCCUUGCGCUUCCCUGGGCUGCGGCCGGCCUUCUCAGAACGAAGGGCGUCCUUCCACCCCGCGGCGCAGGUGACCGCUGCCAUGGCUUUUCCCCAUCGGCCGGACGCCCCUGAGCUGCCUGACUUCUCCAUGCUGAAGAGGCUGGCUCGAGACCAGCUCAUCUAUCUGCUGGAGCAGCUUCCUGGAAAAAAGGAUUUAUUCAUUGAGGCAGAUCUCAUGAGCCCUUUGGAUCGAAUUGCCAAUGUCUCCAUCCUGAAGAUUGUGCUUCUUGGUCAGACCCCGCAUCAAGAAUAUGCGAUACAUUGCCAGUCUUGUCAAUGCUGACAAAUUGGCUGGCCGAACUCGCAAAUACAAAGUGAUCUUCAGCCCUCAAAAGUUCUAUGCGUGUGAGAUGGUGCUUGAGGAAGAGGGAAUCUAUGGAGAUGUGAGCUGUGAUGAAUGGGCCUUCUCUUUGCUGCCUCUUGAUGUGGAUCUGCUGAGCAUGGAACUACCAGAAUUUUUCAGGGAUUACUUUCUGGAAGGAGAUCAGCGUUGGAUCAACACUGUAGCUCAGGCCUUACACCUUCUCAGCACUCUCUAUGGACCCUUUCCAAACUGCUAUGGAAUUGGCAGGUGCGCCAAGAUGGCAUAUGAAUUGUGGAGGAACCUGGAGGAGGAGGAGGAUGGCGAAACCAAGGGCCGAAGGCCAGAGAUUGGACAUAUCUUUCUCUUGGACAGAGAUGUGGACUUUGUGACAGCACUUUGCUCCCAAGUGGUUUAUGAGGGCCUAGUAGAUGACACCUUCCGCAUCAAGUGUGGGAGUGUCGACUUUGGCCCAGAAGUCACAUCCUCUGACAAGAGCCUGAAGGUGCUACUCAAUGCCGAGGACAAGGUGUUUAAUGAGAUUCGGAACGAGCACUUCUCCAAUGUCUUUGGCUUCUUGAGCCAGAAGGCCCGGAACUUGCAGGCCCAGUAUGAUCGCCGGAGAGGCAUGGACAUUAAGCAGAUGAAGAAUUUCGUGUCCCAGGAGCUCAAGGGCCUGAAACAGGAGCACCGCCUGCUGAGUCUCCAUAUUGGGGCCUGUGAAUCCAUCAUGAAGAAGAAAACCAAGCAGGAUUUCCAGGAGCUAAUCAAGACUGAGCAUGCACUGCUAGAGGGGUUCAACAUCCGGGAGAGCACCAGCUACAUUGAGGAACACAUAGACCGGCAGGUGUCGCCUAUAGAAAGCCUGCGCCUCAUGUGCCUUUUGUCCAUCACUGAGAAUGGUUUGAUCCCCAAGGAUUACCGAUCUCUGAAAACACAGUAUCUGCAGAGCUAUGGCCCUGAGCACCUGCUAACCUUCUCCAAUCUGCGAAGAGCUGGGCUCCUAACGGAGCAGGCCCCCGGGGACACCCUCACAGCCGUGGAGAGUAAAGUGAGCAAGCUGGUGACCGACAAGGCUGCAGGAAAGAUUACUGAUGCCUUCAGUUCUCUGGCCAAGAGGAGCAAUUUUCGUGCCAUCAGCAAAAAGCUGAAUUUGAUCCCACGUGUGGACGGCGAGUAUGAUCUGAAAGUGCCCCGAGACAUGGCUUACGUCUUCGGUGGUGCUUAUGUGCCCCUGAGCUGCCGAAUCAUUGAGCAGGUGCUAGAGCGGCGAAGCUGGCAGGGCCUUGAUGAGGUGGUACGGCUGCUCAACUGCAGUGACUUUGCAUUCACAGAUAUGACUAAGGAAGACAAGGCUUCCAGUGAGUCCCUGCGCCUCAUCUUGGUGGUGUUCUUGGGUGGUUGUACAUUCUCUGAGAUCUCAGCCCUCCGGUUCCUGGGCAGAGAGAAAGGCUACAGGUUCAUUUUCCUGACGACAGCAGUCACAAACAGCGCUCGCCUUAUGGAGGCCAUGAGUGAGGUGAAAGCCUGAUGUUUUUCCCGGCCAGUGUUGACAUCUUCCCUGAACACAUUCCUCAGUGAGAUGCAGGCAUCUGGCACCCAGCUGCUAUAACCAAGUGUCCACCAACUACCUGCUAAGAGCCGGGAGCAUGGAACGUGUUGGGAUUUAGAGAACAUUAUCUGAGAAAAGAGUUCACUUCCUGCUCCCAGGAUAUUUCUCUUUUCUGUUUAUGAAGUACAACCCAUGCUGCUAAGAUGCGAGCAGGAAGAGGCAUCCUUUGCUAAAUCCUGUUUGAAUGUCAUUGUAAAUAAAGCCUCUGCUCUCAGAUGUAAUACGUUGGUCGUUCUGGACACGCACUUCCAUCUUUAUUAGUGAAAGCCCAUUGGAGCUUGCUACAGGGGCUUCCUGUGCUUCUUGGCCUGGACUUUGUAGUGGCUCCAGGCCUGGUCUGGUUCUUCCCUGUAAAAAUCACUCUACCACUCUGUACCUGAGUUUCCUCUACCAUAAAAUGAGGGAGAUGGCUGAGGUGACCAGCAAGCACGUUUCCAGUUCUAAAAUGUUGUGAUUCAUUACAUUUUUGAGAAAAUGA